GGCAGACACGGAGACAGCGCCGGGGCGGAGGGUACGAUGGAGAAUUUCACGGCACUGUUUGGGGCUCAGGCUGACCCACCACCGCCCCCAACCGCACUCGGCUUCGGACCAGGAAAGCCUCCACCCCCGCCACCGCCUCCUGCGGGCGGGGGACCCGGCACGGCCCCGCCUCCCACCGCGGCCACGGCUCCUCCUGGCGCGGACAAGUCAGGAGCUGGCUGUGGCCCUUUUUACCUCAUGAGGGAACUGCCAGGUAGCACAGAGCUGACAGGCAGCACGAAUCUGAUCACACACUACAACUUGGAACAAGCCUAUAAUAAAUUCUGUGGGAAGAAGGUGAAGGAGAAGCUAAGUAACUUCCUGCCUGACCUGCCAGGGAUGAUUGAUCUGCCUGGUUCCCAUGAUAACAGCAGCCUCCGCUCUCUCAUUGAGAAGCCCCCUAUUCUCAGUAGCUCUUUCAAUCCUAUCACAGGGACCAUGCUGGCCGGCUUCCGCCUCCACACUGGCCCGUUGCCGGAGCAGUGUCGUCUGAUGCAUAUUCAGCCUCCCAAGAAGAAGAAUAAGCACAAGCACAAACAGAGCCGUACCCAGGAUCCUGUCCCCCCAGGUAAACCCAGUUAAGUUCCGUAUGGAGCUCUGGACUCCUAAAUUCCCCUGAAGAAGAAACCAAUGUACUGUGGUCUCUUGGGACUUGGGACAGGGACUCUAGCAGCACCUCUGUAUCCUUUCUGGCCAUUUGGACAAAAGCAGUUGCCCCGACUUGGGAUUUUCCUGUAGUCUUCAGUGGUUCAUAACAGUAGAGGAUUUUGAGCUUUACAGGUGAUAGGUACCUAAUGUCUCCUACAGAAACACCAUCUGAUUCAGAUCACAAGAAGAAGAAAAAGAAAAAAGAAGAGGAUCCUGAACGGAAAAGGAAGAAGAAAGAGAAGAAGAAAAAGAAGGUAGAGUAGAGGCCUAUUGCCACAACCCAGUGAGUUUCCCCAGAUCUCACCCCUGUCCUAAAUACCCUAGAGUUCUUUGCCUCAAGUUGGACCCAAGAUUGAAAACCCAAGGCAGGUUGCAGGUUUCUCCUGUACAGCCUGAUCAAAGCCAAGGCUAGUUCCUAGUUGUUCUUACCCUGCUUCUUUCUCCCCCAGAAUCGACAUAGUCCAGACCACCCAGGUAUGGGCAGCUCCCAGGCCAGCAGCAGCAGCAGCCUACGCUAAUAGGACCACUGGACUCUUUGCCAGGAUGGCUUUUCCUGCUGUACUGAACCUGCUGAUAAAAGCUGCCUUCCAGGCUCUUGGACACUGCCUUGGGAGCAUCCUGCAGCUGGGACAGAGGCCAGCUCCUGUUGGGCUCAGUUGAGACUAAGUAAAUUAGGAGAGAGAGGGACAUGCUUUUGUAGGCUCAUCCCAGUUGGUUUUCUCAUGGACAUCUCUUCCUCUCCCAGGAAGCUUACAAUUUUCUUCUCUCUCUUUUGUGCAAUUUGUCUGAUUUAGGACUUGUUCUGUGUUUUCUUUAAAAAAAAAAAAAUUACAUUUAUCAAACUGG